AGAGGAAAGAAGAGAGGGGACUGAAGACAGACUUUGAGAGGGCUCAGAAACCCAGUACACCCCCUGUCCCAGCCCUGUCCACCUGCUGCUGUGGCCACAGCGAGAGAAAAGACAGCUAGUAAGAUAGGAAGUGAGGCCAGGUACCUUGUGGGCAGUGAUGUCAUUCGGUGCGACUCCUAAGAUGUCUCCAGAGAUGGGAGAGCUCACCCAAACCAGGUUGCAGAAGAUCUGGAUUCCACACAGCAGCGGCAGCAGCAGGCUGCAACGGAGAAGGGGCUCAUCCAUACCCCAGUUUACCAAUUCCCCCACAAUGGUGAUCAUGGUGGGUUUACCAGCUCGAGGCAAGACCUAUAUCUCCACAAAGCUCACACGAUAUCUCAACUGGAUAGGAACACCAACUAAAGCAAGGACAUUUUUUUGGCCACUGGGAUCUUCCCAACCUCUUCACUGGCACUCCCUGCUUUCAGUGUUUAAUUUAGGCCAGUAUCGACGAGAGGCAGUGAGCUACAAGAACUAUGAAUUCUUUCUUCCAGACAACAUGGAAGCCCUGCAAAUCAGGAAGCAGUGCGCCCUGGCAGCCCUGAAGGAUGUUCACAACUAUCUCAGCCAUGAGGAAGGUCAUGUUGCGGUUUUUGAUGCCACCAACACUACCAGAGAACGACGGUCACUGAUCCUGCAGUUUGCAAAAGAACAUGGUUACAAGGUGUUUUUCAUUGAGUCCAUUUGUAAUGACCCUGGCAUAAUUGCAGAAAACAUCAGGCAAGUGAAACUUGGCAGCCCUGAUUAUAUAGACUGUGACCGGGAAAAGGUUCUGGAAGACUUUCUAAAGAGAAUUGAGUGCUAUGAGGUCAACUACCAACCCUUGGAUGAGGAACUGGACAGCCACCUGUCCUACAUCAAGAUCUUCGACGUGGGCACACGCUACAUGGUGAACCGAGUGCAGGAUCACAUCCAGAGCCGCACAGUCUACUACCUCAUGAAUAUCCAUGUCACACCUCGCUCCAUCUACCUUUGCCGACAUGGCGAGAGUGAACUCAACAUCAGAGGCCGCAUCGGAGGUGACUCUGGCCUCUCAGUUCGCGGCAAGCAGUAUGCCUAUGCCCUGGCCAACUUCAUUCAGUCCCAGGGCAUCAGCUCCCUGAAGGUGUGGACCAGUCACAUGAAGAGGACCAUCCAGACAGCUGAGGCCCUGGGUGUCCCCUAUGAGCAGUGGAAGGCCCUGAAUGAGAUUGAUGCGGGUGUCUGUGAGGAGAUGACCUAUGAAGAAAUCCAGGAACAUUACCCUGAAGAAUUUGCACUGCGAGACCAAGAUAAAUAUCGCUACCGCUAUCCCAAGGGAGAGUCCUAUGAGGAUCUGGUUCAGCGUCUGGAGCCAGUGAUAAUGGAGCUAGAACGACAGGAGAAUGUACUGGUGAUCUGCCACCAGGCUGUCAUGCGGUGCCUCCUGGCCUAUUUCCUGGAUAAAAGUUCAGGUGAAUGCUGGAACAAGGCCCAGAGAGAUGAUGUGACUGAGAAUGCAGACCCACAGAACAUCAGGGCUGGGGCACCCUCAGAGUACAUCUAGUCCAAUCCUGUCCUGUGAAAUGGGAACACUGAGGACCAGAGAGAGAAGAGCCCGGGCCAAGGUCAUUAGUGGAGGCAGUGGCAGAGCUGGGUCAGAGAUCUCAGGCAAGUCACUUCCCUUCUCCGAGUCUGUUUCCUCAAGUGUACAAGGAGGGUGUACAGUAGUACCUCAAUCUAGCUUUAAGGGUGUCAUGAGGUAGUGGGCAAAACACCCUUGGCCCAGGGCCUGAUGAUGACAAAAACAAGGAGGAGCAGCAGGAUGGAUGCCCAGGAAGGAAAAAAGCCAACCUAAUGUCUCAGGAGGCUGGGAGGGCAGUGGCAGACCUCAGAAACCUAGGGUGGAACCUGCUGUUGAGGGAAGCCAUGAGGGUCGGUGAUCCUGCAAAAUGAAGGGAAAUGGGUAGCGUUAUGUGCAGGUGGGCAGGAAAGUGGGUGUCAGGAGAGAGUGCCUAGCAGGUGGGUUUAUCACCCCCAGGACACUGCAAGCCCCUGGAUGGCAGGGGCAGUUGACAGUAGGGGCCAGUGCAUGCAUUCUGGCCUCACAGGGUCCCAGGUUCAAGGCCUUGCUCUGCUGCUUCCUGGCUGUGUGACUUGCGGAGAGCAUUUUCCCUCUCAAGGCCUCAGUUGGCUGAGACCAUGAAAUGGGCUUACUGUCCCCACCUCUUGGGCUUGCCUGAGAAAUGGAAACAUAGACCCAGACAAGAAUGCAUAUGAAUAUUCAGAACAACUUUAUGCAUAAUGUCAAUAACUGGAAACAAGUGAAUGCACAAAUGCUUGUCCAUCACCAGGCCUGAGGCAGGGAUGAUCAGAGGGAGCGGGCCAGGCUGGGAGAAGGCUGUGGGAGCUGUCCACUGCCACAGCAGGGUCUCAAAAAACACUUGCUGACGUGAACUGUGGGCCUUUGUGGUGUGGGGUCUGCUGAAGGCCCCAGGCUUGGGGCGGGAGAGAAGCCUGCCUGGGUCUCAUUUGUCCUGUGAGUGAGGUGGUGGCCGUCUCCAGGGUGGCCGGCCCAACCCUCCUGCAGGACACCCAGUCCAGUCUACCACCAUUUUCCAAGGCAUUCCUGCCUCCCUGCUCUCCUCCUCUCUUCCCAGGUGCUCUCAGUGCUGCCCCUGCAGGGUGUGGGGAGUGGGCCCCUGGUGAGGCCCCACCACGGCAAGGGGACAUGGAAUGGGGAGCAUCCAGCAAGCCUGGGGGCCUGGGGAGGCUGUGUCCUGGCCAGCACCCUGCCUCUGAGGGCUGCUUCCUGUUCC